GCAGCCUGCGACCGAUGGAGCAGGAGGCGCGGGUGCUGAGAGCUGCGGGCGGCUUUGGCCGGGCCCGGCGCCUGCUGGCCUCCGCCUCGUGGGUACCCUGCAUAGUGCUGGGGCUGGUGCUGAGCUCCGAGGAGCUGCUUACCGCGCAGCCCGCGCCCCACUGCCGACCGGACCCCACGCUGUUGCCCCCAGCGCUGCGCGCCCUGCGCGGACCCGCGCUGCUGGACGCCGCCAUCCCGCGCCUGGGGCCCACGCGAGCCGCGAGCCCCUGCCUGCUCCUGCGCUACCCCGAUCCCGCGCCCUGCACCCGCCCCGGGCCCGCGCCCCGCGCCCGCACGCAACGGCACCCGGCCCUGCACACGCGGCUGGCUCUACGCGCUGCCCGGCGCCGGCCUCCUGCAAAGCCCGGUCACCCAGUGGAACCUUGUGUGUGGAGACGGCUGGAAGGUCCCGCUGGAGCAGGUGAGCCACCUCCUGGGCUGGCUGCUGGGCUGUGUCAUCCUGGGAGCAGGCUGUGACCGGUUUGGACGCCGGGCAGUUUUUGUGGCCUCCCUGGUGCUGACCACAGGCCUGGGGGCCAGUGAGGCCCUGGCUGCCAGCUUCCCUACCCUGCUGGUCCUGCGCCUACUCCACGGGGGCACAUUGGCAGGGGCCCUCCUCGCCCUGUAUCUGGCUCGCCUGGAGUUGUGUGACCCUCCCCACCGCCUGGCCUUCUCCAUGGGGGCUGGCCUUUUCUCGGUGGUGGGCACCCUGCUGCUGCCCGGCCUGGCUGCGCUUGUGCAGGACUGGCGUCUUCUGCAGGGGCUGGGUGCCCUGAUGAGUGGACUCUUGCUGCUCUUUUGGGGGUUCCCGGCCCUGUUCCCCGAGUCUCCCUGCUGGCUGCUGGCCACAGGUCAGGUAGCUCGAGCCAGGAAGAUCCUGUGGCGCUUUGCAGAAGCCAGUGGCGUGGGCCCCGGGGACAGUUCCUUGGAGGAGAACUCCCUGGCUACAGAGCUGACCAUGCUGUCUGCACGGAGCCCCCAGCCCCGGUACCACUCCCCACUGGGGCUUCUGCGUACCCGAGUCACCUGGAGAAACGGGCUUAUCUUGGGCUUCAGCUCGCUGGUUGGUGGAGGCAUCAGAGCUAGCUUCCGCCGCAGCCUGGCACCUCAGGUGCCGACCUUCUACCUGCCCUACUUCCUGGAGGCCGGCCUGGAGGCGGCAGCCUUGGUCUUCCUGCUCCUGACGGCAGAUUGCUGUGGACGCCGCCCCGUGCUGCUGCUGGGCACCAUGGUCACAGGCCUGGCAUCCCUGCUGCUCCUCGCUGGGGCCCAGUGUGAGCUUGGGGCCCCGCAGGCCAUACAGGAGCCAUUGUGUUUGGGCCGACGGUCUGCCACACCAGGGGGCCAUAGUGCCGACAGGGGAGCAGCCUGGGGUGGCAGCCCAAGGCCAGCUGCUGUUUGUUUUCCUCUGAUCCUUGUGGAAGGCCCAAAAGGAUCUUUUGUGACUGGCCUAAAAUCUGCCAGGCUGGACUGUGCUGUUCCUCUCUGUCCUGGGGCUCCUGGCCUCCCGGGCUGUGUCCGCACUCAGCAGCCUCUUCGCGGCCGAGGUCUUCCCCACGGUGAUCAGGGGGGCCGGGCUGGGCCUGGUGCUGGGGGCCGGGUUCCUGGGCCAGGCAGCCGGCCCCCUGGACACCCUGCACGGCCGGCAGGGCUUCUUCCUGCAACAAGUCGUCUUCGCCUCCCUUGCUGUCCUUGCCCUGCUGUGUGUCCUGCUGCUGCCUGAGAGCCGAAGCCGGGGGCUGCCCCAGUCACUGCAGGACGCCGACCGCCUGCGCCGCUCCCCACUCCUGCGGGGCCGCCCCCGCCAGGACCACCUGCCUCUGCUGCCGCCCUCCAACUCCUACUGGGCCGGCCACACCCCCGAGCAGCACUAGUCCUGCCUGGUGGCCCUGGGAGCCAGGAUGGGACCAAAGUCAAGGCCUGGGGCAUGGCUGAGUACCCCAGACGUCUGGUCCAGGGCAGACACAUUCCUCUCAGAAGCCCGUGUCUCAGUGCAGGUGGAGCCGUGGGGACAGCGUGAAGGUGUCUCCAGCCAGGCCCCAGGCACUGGGAGGCCCUGGGUCUCCCCCCAGCCACACCCAGUAGGUGUGGAGGAUAAAGGCUUCUGUGGAA